UCGAAGAGUUUCUUAGACCCAGGGGACAGCCUGCGGGAACCCAGGGGUGGGACGGAAAAGAUCACUGGGGAAUGCCAGGGCUGGGUGUGCUGCUCUAAGACAUUUAAAGUAGUUGGCCAGCAGGAGCAUUUCUUUGUGAAAGCUCAAGGCUUAAAAAAAAUAAUAAUAUGAAAUAUGUAAUAUAUUCAUAUGGCUGGGAUAUUAAAAAUAUAAAAAGUUACCAGUGAAAGAUUUCUUCCCAUCCCGCUUAGGUAUCUUCCUAGGCCCUACCCUCUUAGGUAACCACUUUUGUUCCUUUGUAUCUUUUCCGAAUUUCUGCAAAUACUGGCAAAUAUAACUAGUUAGUUCCCCCUUUUUUCACACAGGUGAUAGAAAUCCUUCUAACUCCUUGAUUCUUUCACUUUAUCUUACUGGUCUCUACAUGUCAGAACACAGAAGUUGUGUUUUGUUUCGUUUUGUUUUACAGAGCUGUGUGUCACAUUUGAAGACGAGCACUGAGGAUGAGGAACCAACUGAAGAAUAUGAAAAUGUUGGAAAUGCAGCAUCUAAGUGGCCAAAAGUGGAGGAUCCUAUGCCUGAAUCUAAGGUUGGUGACACAUGUGUUUGGGAUAGCAAGGUAGAGAAUCAACAGAAAAAGCCUGUGGAAAACAGGAUGAAGGAGGACAAAAGCAGCAUCAGGGAAGCAAUCAGCAAAGCCAAGAGUACAGCAAAUAUAAAGACAGAACAGGAAGGUGAGGCAUCUGAGAAGAGCUUGCAUCUGAGCCCACAGCAUAUCACACACCAGACUAUGCCUAUAGGACAGAGAGGCAGUGAGCAAGGCAAACGUGUGGAGAACAUUAAUGGAACCUCCUACCCUAGUCUACAGCAGAAAACCAAUGCUGUUAAGAAAUUACAUAAAUGUGAUGAAUGUGGGAAAUCCUUCAAAUAUAAUUCCCGCCUUGUUCAACAUAAAAUUAUGCACACUGGGGAAAAGCGCUAUGAAUGUGAUGACUGUGGAGGGACUUUCCGGAGCAGCUCGAGCCUUCGGGUCCACAAACGGAUCCACACUGGGGAGAAGCCGUACAAGUGUGAGGAAUGUGGGAAAGCCUACAUGUCCUACUCCAGCCUUAUAAACCACAAAAGCACCCAUUCUGGGGAGAAGAACUGUAAAUGUGAUGAAUGUGGAAAAUCCUUCAAUUAUAGCUCUGUUCUGGACCAGCAUAAAAGGAUCCACACUGGGGAGAAGCCCUAUGAAUGUGGUGAGUGUGGGAAGGCCUUCAGGAACAGCUCUGGGCUCAGAGUCCACAAAAGGAUCCACACGGGGGAGAAGCCCUAUGAAUGCGACAUCUGUGGGAAAACCUUCAGUAACAGCUCUGGCCUUAGGGUCCAUAAAAGGAUCCACACAGGUGAGAAACCUUACGAAUGUGAUGAGUGUGGGAAGGCCUUCAUUACUUGUAGAACACUUCUCAACCAUAAAAGCAUCCACUUUGGAGAUAAACCCUAUAAAUGUGAUGAGUGUGAGAAAUCUUUUAAUUAUAGCUCUCUUCUCAUUCAGCAUAAAGUCAUCCACACUGGAGAGAAACCUUAUGAAUGUGAUGAAUGUGGGAAGGCUUUCAGGAACAGCUCAGGCCUCAUAGUGCAUAAAAGGAUCCACACAGGAGAGAAACCUUACAAGUGUGAUGUCUGUGGCAAAGCAUUCAGCUAUAGCUCAGGCCUCGCAGUCCAUAAAAGCAUUCACCCUGGGAAGAAAGCCCAUGAAUGUAAGGAGUGUGGGAAAUCCUUUAGUUAUAACUCACUACUUCUUCAACACAGAACUAUUCAUACCGGAGAGAGACCUUAUGUAUGUGAUGUGUGUGGGAAAACGUUCAGAAACAAUGCAGGCCUCAAAGUCCACAGGAGGCUCCAUACUGGGGAAAAACCAUAUAAGUGUGAUGUGUGUGGGAAAGCCUAUAUCUCACGCUCUAGCCUUAAAAAUCACAAAGGAAUCCACCUUGGGGAGAAGCCCUAUAAAUGUAGCUAUUGUGAGAAAUCCUUCAACUACAGCUCUGCCCUUGAACAGCAUAAAAGGAUUCAUACCAGGGAAAAACCCUUUGGGUGUGAUGAGUGUGGUAAAGCUUUCAGAAAUAAUUCUGGCCUUAAAGUACAUAAACGAAUCCACACUGGGGAACGACCUUACAAAUGUGAAGAAUGUGGGAAAGCAUACAUCUCUCUCUCGAGCCUUAUAAAUCAUAAAAGUGUACACCCUGGGGAGAAGCCCUUUAAGUGUGACGAGUGUGAGAAGGCCUUCAUCACAUACCGAACCCUUACAAACCACAAAAAAGUUCAUCUUGGGGAGAAGCCCUACAAAUGUGAUGUGUGUGAGAAAUCUUUUAAUUACACAUCGCUCCUUUCUCAGCACAGAAGGGUCCACACUAGAGAGAAACCCUAUGAAUGUGACAGGUGUGAGAAGGUCUUCAGAAACAACUCAAGCCUUAAAGUUCAUAAAAGAAUCCAUACUGGGGAGAGGCCCUAUGAAUGUGAUGUGUGUGGAAAAGCCUACAUCUCACACUCAAGCCUUAUUAACCAUAAGAGUACCCACCCUGGCAGGACACCCCAUACAUGUGAUGAAUGUGGAAAAGCUUUUUUCUCAAGCAGAACUCUUAUAAGCCAUAAAAGAGUCCAUCUUGGGGAGAAACCCUUCAAGUGUGUUGAGUGUGGGAAAUCUUUCAGUUACAGCUCUCUCCUUUCUCAGCACAAGAGGAUCCACACAGGGGAGAAACCCUAUGUGUGUGAUAGGUGUGGGAAGGCCUUCAGGAACAGCUCAGGCCUCACAGUGCAUAAAAGGAUCCACACAGGAGAGCUCCCGUACUUGAGCUCCAGCUGAACCUAAUGCACUGUCUACUUUUGGGGAGAUGCAGGCUAAAUAACAAAGGAGAGGAUGGCCACAGCUCAGGUGGGGAUUCUGAGUGCCUCAGCCCCACUAAGCACCAGACAAGCUCCUACUGCGGCCCCCAUCUACUCGCAUGCUCCAGAAAUGGGCCCAGGUCCUCAAGUGUACCUACAGCCAGAUACAAGCCAUUCAGGCUGAUCCCAGACAUGGUGGGGUCUCCCUUGUAGCACAGACCCAAUGAACUGGUGCGGCUGAGCCUGCUCAGACCAGGGAUGGAACAUGGUUUAGGCACCACCCCCGGUUCCUUCCAGAGAACGAUAUGCAAGUGGGAAAAAUAAAGGGGGAGGGAAAAGCGGGGAGGAGAAAGAGAAAAGAAAAGCCUGAAAAAACAGUGAGUAUGGAAUAGCCUUCCAUAGGAGUGCAUGUCUCUAUUAGCAAAUUUGUCUGAAGGUGAAAGCCUGGAAAAUAAUUUCAUGUUUUGUGUAUGAAGACACUGGGCGUGAAACGGUACUGAACACCAAUCCUGCAAUGCAGGGGAAUUUUCCUCCGUGGGAUUCAGAAAUGAGAGGAUCACCACCAGGACAACACCUGAAGAUGGUGUUAGCUGAAGGCAGACAUUGGGGACCUGAAGUCUGUCUGCAUCAAGACCUUGAGUAAUUGGCCACAGCUGUACCCAAGGAGUUCCUGGGCUGGGGAGACCCUUCAUUUCUCUUCUCCAGCUUCAGCUAAAGGCCUAGAGACAUGGAGAAGGAAGCAGAAUACAGUACUUCAAUUGUCUUCCUACUGAGGAGCCAUUCUCAUUUAGACCUGGCGGUUCUCAGGUCUGGAUAGUGUCAUUGUGCGAAGGAAGCCGUUUGCAUGAAACCUGUGUAGAGUCAGUGAAGUAUAGUGGCCGAGGACAUGGUCUCCACAAGGAAGCCUGAGUUCAAAUAAGGACUUUCACUUAUUUCCAGAUGACUUUAGGCAAGUAACUAAACUUGUGUGUCCUCACGUGUCUUUUUUUUUUUUUUUUUUUUUUUUUUUUUUUUUUUUAAGACGGUCUCGUUCUGUCGCCCAGGCUGGAGUGCAGGGGCAUUAGCUCACUGCAGUCUCCACCUCCUGAGCUCAAGCAAUUCUCAUGCCUCAGCCUCCAGAGUAGCUGGGAUUACAGGCAUGCGCCACCAUGCCAGGCUAACUUUGGUAUUUUUGGUAGAGAAAGGGUUUCAUCAUUGUUGGCUGGGCUGGUCUUGAACUCCUGACCUCAAGUAAUCUGCCCAGCCUCAGACUCCCAAGGUGCUGAGAUUACAGGCCUGAACCACCACAGGCUACCAUACUGGGCCCUCACCUGUCUUUUGUAAAGAUAAUAGUAGCAACCUCAGGUUGUAAUGAGGGUUGGAAACAUUAAUAGUGUUAAGGUCCUUAGAAGGCUGCCUAGAAUGAGAAGUAUUUGCAUAAGAAUGUAUGGAAUAAGUCUGAAGUGUGGUGGCCCUGUCCAAAGACUCAGCAUCUAGAUGCUUGGGCAGUGGAGGACAACUCUUACCUGGAAGUCAAGGAAAUCCCUCAAGGACCACCCCCUACUCAGACAAAACUUGAGAAGAAACAUGAGAAAAGUUAUUUUUUGGAUGUUCCUGAGUGGUAUCUUGCUUCUAAGUAAGCAAUCCAUUGUCUCUAAACAAACAUGUUUUGUCUUUGUCGGGCUGCAAAAGGGCUCAGCAGGAGGAGCCUCCAGCUGAGGCCAGUAACCACACGUUGGGGGUUGAGGGCUGCCUCACGCUUGCCUUUCUGGCCUGGGCAGCCUGCUCACUCACAUGGUACACAUCUUGUUUCCCCUGUGUUUUCCCAGCAAUAUUCAGAUGUGCUGGAGAUUACUGUAGGAAGGGUUGGUGAGAGCCAGACUUUUACCAUCUUAACCAUGGCUAUUUCUGGUGAGUGUCCCUUAAGAUCUCAGAGGAUAAGUAGUGGUCCUGGGGUGGGCAGGGCAAAGCCCCAGAGAGGAGCAGGUGAAGUUCCUCUGGUCUUGGGUGCAAACCAUGGGGCCAUAUUCCAUUCAGUGCAAUAAUAUGGAUUUAUUUCCUGUUCUGUCAUUUUCCCAUCUGUAAAAUGAGGGAAAAGACCUGUUUACAAGAUUAUUUUAAGGCUUAAUAAAAAUGCUCUGUACUUUAUAAAAA